AUGCGUGCAGCAAAGAAUGGAGGAGUCGGAACCCGAACGGAAGCGGGCUCGCACCGACGAGGUGCCUGCCGGAGGAAGCCGCUCCGAGGCGGAAGAUGAGGACGACGAGGACUACGUGCCCUAUGUGCCGUUACGGCAGCGCCGGCAGCUACUGGUGAGGGGCACGCGUCCGGGGAGGGAUGGGGCCGUGACCGCGGGGUCGCAGGGGGCGGGCGUGGCCUCGGCCUCCGUGGGGAGGAGGGCAGUCUGAGGAGUGAGCUUCAGUACACCAGGGCGCGGCCCCCAGACAAACGAGGGACCGACGGCUUGAUCUGAGGGGUAGGGCAGCUUUGCGCCUCGGGCACAGGAUCCUCGCCCCAAAGCCAGGAUCCUGACGCUGACCUUGUGGACUCCAUGCCCAUCCUAUCUGUGGAUCCCGGGUGGAACCUCAGCUCCAGAAGCUGCUGCAGCGAAGACGCAAGGGAGCUGCGGAGGAAGAGCAGCAGGACAGCGGUAGUGAACCCCGGGGAGAUGAGGACGACAUCCCGCUAGGCCCUCAGUCCAACGUCAGCCUCCUGGAUCAGCACCAGCACCUUAAAGAGAAGGCUGAAGCGCGCAAAGAGUCUGCCAAGGAGAAGCAGCUGAAGGAAGAAGAGAAGAUCCUGGAGAGUGUUGCCGAGGGCCGAGCAUUGAUGUCAGUGAAGGAGAUGGCUAAGGGCAUUACGUAUGAUGACCCCAUCAAAACCAGCUGGACUCCACCCCGUUAUGUUCUGAGCAUGUCUGAAGAGCGACAUGAGCGCGUGCGGAAGAAAUACCACAUCCUGGUGGAGGGAGACGGUAUCCCACCACCCAUCAAGAGCUUCAAGGAAAUGAAGUUUCCUGCAGCCAUCCUGAGAGGCCUGAAGAAGAAAGGCAUUCACCACCCAACACCCAUUCAGAUCCAGGGCAUCCCCACCAUUCUAUCUGGCCGUGACAUGAUAGGCAUCGCUUUCACGGGUUCAGGCAAGACACUGGUGUUCACGUUGCCCGUCAUCAUGUUCUGCCUGGAACAAGAGAAGAGGUUACCCUUCUCAAAGCGCGAGGGGCCCUAUGGACUCAUCAUCUGCCCCUCGCGGGAGCUGGCCCGGCAGACCCAUGGCAUCCUGGAGUACUACUGCCGCCUGCUGCAGGAGGACAGCUCACCACUCCUGCGCUGCGCCCUCUGCAUUGGGGGCAUGUCCGUGAAAGAGCAGAUGGAGACCAUCCGACACGGUGUACACAUGAUGGUGGCCACCCCGGGGCGCCUCAUGGAUUUGCUGCAGAAGAAGAUGGUCAGCCUAGACAUCUGUCGCUACCUGGCCCUGGACGAGGCUGACCGCAUGAUCGACAUGGGCUUCGAGGGUGACAUCCGUACCAUCUUCUCCUACUUCAAGGGCCAGCGACAGACCCUGCUCUUCAGUGCCACCAUGCCGAAGAAGAUUCAGAACUUUGCUAAGAGUGCCCUUGUAAAGCCUGUGACCAUCAAUGUGGGGCGCGCUGGGGCUGCCAGCCUGGAUGUCAUCCAGGAGGUAGAAUAUGUGAAGGAGGAGGCCAAGAUGGUGUACCUGCUCGAGUGCCUGCAGAAGACACCCCCGCCUGUACUCAUCUUUGCAGAGAAGAAGGCAGACGUGGACGCCAUCCACGAGUACCUGCUGCUCAAGGGGGUUGAGGCCGUAGCCAUCCAUGGGGGCAAAGACCAGGAGGAACGGACUAAGGCCAUCGAGGCAUUCCGGGAGGGCAAGAAGGAUGUCCUAGUAGCCACAGACGUUGCCUCCAAGGGCCUGGACUUCCCUGCCAUCCAGCACGUCAUCAAUUAUGACAUGCCAGAGGAGAUUGAGAACUAUGUACACCGGAUUGGCCGCACCGGGCGCUCGGGAAACACAGGCAUCGCCACUACCUUCAUCAACAAAGCGUGUGAUGAGUCAGUGCUGAUGGACCUCAAAGCGCUGCUGCUAGAAGCCAAGCAGAAGGUGCCGCCCGUGCUGCAGGUGCUGCAUUGCGGGGAUGAGUCCAUGCUGGACAUUGGAGGAGAGCGCGGCUGUGCCUUCUGCGGGGGCCUGGGUCAUCGGAUCACUGACUGCCCCAAACUCGAGGCUAUGCAGACCAAGCAGGUCAGCAACAUCGGUCGCAAGGACUACCUGGCCCACAGCUCCAUGGACUUCUGAGCCGACAGUCUUCCCUUCUCUCCAAGAGGCCUCAGUCCCCAAGACUGCCACCAGUCUACACAUACAGCAGCCCCCUGGACAGAAUCAGCAUUUCAGCUCAGCUGGCCUGGGAUGGGCCAGGCUGGUCCUGGCUGCCUGUUCCCUGUGCUCUUCAGAAUUACUGUUUUUGUUUCCUUUUACCCCAGCUGCCAUUAAAGCCCAAACCUCUAGCCCA